GUGCCGGAGGACAAGGUGAACCCGCAGCCGGACUUCUGCUGCACUGGGGCUCCGAAUGACCCAGAAUCUGGGGUGGGCUUAGGCCCCGGGCCGCGUGUUCUUGCCACGAGAACCCCUAGCAGCCUGGCCUUGGAAUGGCUGGAUGAGGUGCAUUCGUUGGUUCAUUCAGAUACUGUUAAGAGCCAGCUGUGUGCUAGGAGUGAGAUGGCCUCAAUCUUGCGAAGCCCUCAGGCUCUCCAGCUCACUCUAGCCCUGAUCAAGCCUGACGCAGUCGCCCAUCCACUGAUUCUGGAGGCUGUUCAUCAGCAGAUUCUAAGCAACAAGUUCCUGAUUGUACGAAUGAGAGAACUACUGUGGAGAAAGGAAGAUUGCCAGAGGUUUUACCGAGAGCAUGAAGGGCGUUUUUUCUAUCAGAGGCUGGUGGAGUUCAUGGCCAGCGGGCCAAUCCGAGCCUACAUCCUUGCCCACAAGGAUGCCAUCCAGCUCUGGAGGACGCUCAUGGGACCCACCAGAGUGUUCCGAGCACGCCAUGUGGCCCCAGAUUCUAUCCGUGGGAGUUUCGGCCUCACUGACACCCGCAACACCACCCAUGGUUCGGACUCUGUGGUUUCAGCCAGCAGAGAGAUUGCAGCCUUCUUCCCUGACUUCAGUGAACAGCGCUGGUAUGAGGAGGAAGAGCCCCAGUUGCGCUGUGGCCCUGUGUGCUAUAGCCCAGAGGGAGGUGUCCACUAUGUAGCUGGAACAGGAGGCCUAGGACCAGCCUGAUGCAGGUCUAUGAAGACCAGUGGUAGUGCCCAGACUUCUCCUAGACAUCUAGUCUAAAACAUUCUCCUAGGACCAGGGAAGCCUGGCUUACAGUGCCAUUUCUGCUGGGCACCACCACCUGCCUGAGGGCCUAGCUCACCACAGCACAUCCUCCAGGAUCUAGCCUUCUAUCUACCUCUUCUCUGGAAUGUUUAUGGUGGUUCAGAAGAAUGAUGACUCCUCUUUGCUGAGAACUGUUCAUCCUUCUUCAAGAAGAAGCUUGCCAGGCCGGGCACGGUGGCUCACGCCUAUAAUCCCAGCACUUUGGGAGGCCGAGGCAGGCGGAUCACAAGGUCAGGAAUUCGAGACCAGCCUGACCAACAUGGUGAAACCCCAUCUCUACUAAAAAUACAACAAUUAGCCAGGCAUGGUGGUGCAUGCCUGUAAUCCCAGCUACUCAGAGGCUGAGGCAGGAGAAUUGCUUGAACCUGGGAGGCAGAGGGUGCAGUGAGCCGAGAUCGUGCCAUUGCACUCCAGCCUGGGCGACAUUCUGUCUCAAAAAAAAAAAAAAAGAAGCUUGUCUAAUUGACUUGCCUAAAAAAUGCAGUGACUCCAAACAACAUUUGACCUGUCUUCCUCAAUAAAAGUCAGUGUUCUCCUGAAUCCUUUAUGCUGCCACAUUUAGGGGAAACUUUUCAGGCUUCAUCAUUCUGACUUCUCAGCAGCAUUCAGUUAUUGCUUCAUUCUCCAGAAACACUCUCUUCUCUUGGAUUUUCUGAUCCCACACCCUUGGUUUUCUCCUUCUGUGUGUUUUUCUUCAUCUCCUUUAUCAGCUUAUGCAAACAUUUAUUUUCAUAAAUUCUCUAUUCAAGACAUACUGAAAAAUGCAAAGAUGGUUAAGACAUGAUUGGGUCCUCAAGUUGCUAAUUAUGAAUUUGGGUGGUCAGCCAGCUAUAACGUGGCAGAGAUGGAGAAGUGCCCUAACAGAGGUAUAAAGUCCUGUGGGAGAACAGAGGAAAGAAGGUUUCCUUUGGCUGGGUGAGGAGGUGAAGGAGAUAGGGUGGAAAGUCUUUUAUAAAAGAUAUAGCUGGCUUUGGAACUAAGCCUGAAGGUCAAAUAGGGUAUCCAUAGCAGGGGUCUGGGGCACUAGACAGUCUGUUCAUUUUCAGGAAUAUAUGGGUCAGUUUUGUAUGUGUGACCUAAGAAACCUGUGACACUUCUUACAGGUCUUGACUUUUCUUUCUCAGUACAUGUGUAUUUCUCUUUUUGGUGGCCUUGAAACCUUUGAGUUGAAAAUUGCCUUCACCAUCUGCCACUUUCACUAAUGGUAGACCAGGAAAUUUGGACCCACUGAACAUAGAGAACAACUAGAAAAGCUGUGCAAAAUAUAAACAGCAUCUAUCUGAAAGCAUCAGCUGGCAAUAUAGAACCAAAAUUCAGGACACGAAGGAAACUCAAGAGAAGUGAGCCUGGGACUUAGAGCUACUUUUCCCAUAAGGGCACCUGCUGAUUCUGGAAGAGGCAGCUAAGAAGCUGAGUAGAACUUUCAACAACUUCUUGUGUUAGGGAGCCAGCUUCAUGAAUGCUGGCAGAAAACACAGGAUUACUUGGGCAGAGACUACUGCUCAGGGCACAGCAGGCAGUGUGUUAGCCUUGGUCUCCCUUGCCCUCCAAGUCCCACAGGGCAAUACUGGCAGGCCCAGGAAAGUGUUACACACUGCAGGUUUGCAUGACGGCUAAGGAACCACAAUCUUAGGGAGAUACUAUCUCUGUCUUCUAAGGCCAUUUGCUGUACAAAAAUCCUUGAAAUACCUGGGCACAGUGGCACACCUAUAAUCCUAGCACUUUGGGAGGCUGAGGCAGGCGGAUCACCUGAGGUUGGGAGUUCCAGACCAGCCUGACCAACAUGGAGAAAUCCCGUCUCUACUAAAAAUACAAAAAUUAGCCAAGCGUGGUGGCGCGAGCCUGUAAUCCAGCUACUCGGGAGGCUGAGGCAGGAGAAUCGCUUGAACCCAGGAGGCGGAGGUUGUGGUGAGCCAAGAUCACGCCGUUGCACUCCAGCCUGGGCAACAAGAGUGAAACUCCAUCUCAAGAAAAAAAAAAUCCUUGAAAUAGUCUGGAACAAAAUCUGUCAACAUCUCAGCCCACAAAGUAUCAACAAAAUUGAUAUUUUGUUGCAUUUAAAAAAUUUAAAUGGUGGUCAAAGCGUACAAAAUCUGACAAUUAAGACACCCACAAGAGACACAGAAUUAUCUCCCAAUAAAAUUGUCUCAUAAAAACCUGGCUCCCACAAAUAUGGAAAGGGAGAAAACUAGAAUAAACCCUGUGGUGUCGAAUUGGA